CGUCUGUUCAUGGAAAAUUUUGCUGCAGGUGUCAGCGGCGCUGGUAAUUCCUGAGCUCAGGUGAUCCCGUAAUUCUCCCUCUCCGCUCAUCACUGACGAGUAACCUCUUCGCUUUGCUUACAGCCGGCAAACAUUUCUGCCUGGUUUUCACUCGCUAUUUAAAUAGGCAACCGUUCCCGAGACUCCCUGUCACAGUUUCUAACGACCUUCCCUUUCCCACCCUGCCGCCUUAGGGAAGGAAUCAGACACGUGCGGUGGAGUAAGUGAAGCCUGCAAUUCCUAGCUAUGGAAAGGUCCAAAGAAGUCGGCCUGGUGCAACAGGGUGCACGCAGCUGCCCAUAAUCACUUUGGCUCCACUUCUGGUUUUUGUUUUGUUUUGUUUUGUUUUUUGUUUUUUACCAACUAUUCAGUUCAAAUGCUAUCAGCCACGCAAAGGAACGUGGUCCAAAUAAUUUUUAGAGUAUAUAUUUGCCUUUUCUUCUGUCAUAGUCCCAGCCAGUAAUAUACAGAUAACGCUUGCUAAGUAGAUGCCAAUAUGCUACUUAAACACUGGCAAUUACUGCUAAGACUAAUAAAGAAGCAGAUGUAGCUUUUGCUUUUAGUAUCAAUUGGUAUUCAUGGGCAUUUCAUUCUUUCUUUCUUUCUUUUUUUCUUUUUUUUUGAGACGGAGUCUCUGUUGCCCAGGCUGGAGUGCAGUGGGGCGAUCUCGGCUCACUGCAAUCUCUGCUUCCUGGGUUCAAGCCAUUCUCCUGGCUCAGCCUCCCGAGUAGCUGGGAUUACAGGCACGCACCACCACACCUAGCAAAUUUUUGUAUUUUUAGUAGAGACGGGGUUUCACCAUAUUAGCCAGGAUGGUCUCAAUCUCCUGACCUCGUGAUCCGCCUGCCUCAGCCUCCCAAAGUGCUGGGAUUAUAGGUGUAAGCCACCGCGCCCGGCCUCAUUUCAUUCUUUCUUAAACCUUCUAAGUCAGAAAUGAAGAGUGCCUCAUGCUAGAUGUGACUUUGCCAUGCCAAGGGGAUGAUCAAAAUAAGUUACCAGUUUCCUUUCUCCUCCUUUUUUAAGAAAAUAGGGGCGGGCACGGUGGCUCACGCCUGUAAUCCCUACACUUUCGGAGGCUGAGGCGGGCAGAUCAUGAAGUUAGGAGUUCAAGACUAGCCUGGCCAACAUAGUGAAACUUGAACCCCGGAGGUGGAGGUCGCAGUGAGCCGACAUCGCGCCAUUGCACUCCAGCUUGGGCAACAGAGUGAGACUUCGUCUCAAAAAUAAAAUAAAAUAAAUAAAGCAGUAUGAUUAAUUUUGAAGAAGCCCUUUUGCCUCUAAAAUAGUUGUUAAUUUUCACCCAAUUGGAGCCCCUCAAAGUGUACCCUACCAACCCAAAUUAUUCAAAUAAAGCACAGUGGCUUGUUAUCAACAACAACCAAAUCUAUGUUUUUUGAUCAUUUACAUGCCGAGGACUGUAUUCUGAAUUCUUUAUGAUAAAUUUAAAUUAAUUUUUCAAUUUUAGCCCUAGCUCACCAUAAUAGUAACUAACAGCACUUACUGUGUGCCAGAUACUAUUCUAAGGACCAAACAUACUUCAUUUAAUCUUCCCAGCAACCCCGAUGGAUACCAUUAUCUCCAUCUACACAGCGGGGAACUGAAGCACAGGAGAUAUAUUUUUGCCAUCAUGGAUCAGUUUGGAGAUAUAUUAGAAGGUGAAGUGGACCAUUCUUUCUUUGACAGUGACUUUGAAGAAGGAAAGAAAUGUGAAACUAACUCAGUUUUUGACAAGCAAAAUGAUGACCCAAAGGAAAGAAUAGAUAAAGAUACAAAAAAUGUAAAUUCGAACACUGGAAUGCAAACAACAGAAAAUUAUCUUACUGAGAAGGGAAAUGAAAGAAACGUGAAAUUUCCCCCAGAACACCCCGUAGAGAAUGAUGUUACACAAACUGUAAGUUCUUUCUCAUUGCCAGCCUCUUCAAGAUCAAAAAAAUUGUGUGAUGUUACAACAGGACUUAAAAUACACGUGUCCAUUCCAAAUAGAAUUCCCAAAAUUGUAAAAGAAGGUGAAGAUGAUUACUACACAGAUGGAGAGGAAAGCAGUGAUGAUGGGAAGAAAUACCAUGUGAAGUCCAAGUCCGCUAAACCAUCUACUAACGUUAAAAAAAGCAUAAGGAAAAAGUAUUGCAAAGUUAGCUCCUCUUCCUCCUCCUCUUUAUCUUCCUCAUCUUCAGGUUCAGGUACAGAUUGUUUAGAUGCAGGGUCUGAUAGCCAUCUAUCUGAUUCGUCUCCGUCAUCUAAGUCAUCUAAGAAACAUGUAUCUGGUAUAACCCUCCUGUCACCAAAACACAAGUAUAAAUCAGGAAUAAAAUCGACAGAAACACAGCCUUCAAGUACUACACCAAAAUGUGGCCACUACCCUGAGGAGUCUGAAGAUACUGUGACUGACGUAAGUCCCUUAUCAACUCCAGACAUUAGCCCUCUUCAGUCUUUUGAACUGGGCAUAGCAAAUGAUCAAAAAGUGAAAAUUAAAAAGCAAGAAAAUGUGAGCCAAGAAAUAUAUGAAGAUGUUGAGGAUUUGAAAAAUAAUUCAAAAUAUUUGAAAGCAGCCAAAAAAGGGAAAGAAAAACAUGAGCCUGAUGUCUCCUCAAAGUCGUCUUCAGUGUUAGACUCCAGUUUAGACCACAGACAUAAACAGAAAGUCUUACAUGACACAAUGGAUCUGAAUCAUCUCUUGAAAGCUUUUCUGCAAUUAGAUAAAAAAGGACCACAAAAACAUCACUUUGAUCAGCCUUCAGUAGCACCCGGGAAAAACUACUCUUUCACAAGAGAAGAGGUGAGACAGAUCGAUCGGGAAAAUCAGAGGCUUUUGAAAGAACUGUCAAGACAGGCGGAAAAGCCGGGAAGCAAAAGUACAAUUCCUAGAUCGGCUGAUCAUCCCCCAAAGUUAUAUCACAGUGCUCUCAACAGACAGAAGGAACAACAAAGGAUUGAGAGAGAAAACUUGGCUUUAUUGAAAAGGCUUGAGGCCGUGAAACCAACAGUUGGUAUGAAACGUUCAGAACAACUGAUGGACUAUCAUCGCAAUAUGGGCUAUCUCAACUCAUCACCAUUGUCAAGACGGGCCAGAUCCACUCUUGGCCAAUAUAGCCCAUUAAGAGCUUCCAGGACAUCCAGUGCUACGAGUGGUCUCAGUUGUAGGAGUGAGCGAUCAGCGGUUGACCCCUCCAGUGGCCACCCUCGAAGAAGACCUAAACCCCCUAAUGUCCGUACAGCUUGGUUAUAAAACACUUUUUUACUUUAAACAUUGUUCACACAACUUUUCUUGAAGUGCUCGUGCAUAUUCCUAUAAUUCUCUGUGUAAACAUCUAGAAUACCGUUUUAGCAAUUGAAGGUGUACAACAGUGAGUUGUAAUGUAUUGUUAUUCAGUGCAAAAUUAUUGUCAAAAAACGAUUUAAUGUAAAAAGUGUUUCCUGAGGAUGUAUUUAUAUGAGAUGUAUGUGUUCUUAAUAGAGAAAUAGUGGUAUGCAUGUGUAUCUUCUAAUUAUUCAGUUGUCAUGCUGUCAAAAUAGUAGUGAUAGUAUCAUUGCAUGUCGUACCCAAGAUGGUCACUAUAGUUUUCAAUUUGUGUUAUUUUCAUUUCUUUAUAAGUGUUAUACCAUGAGCUCAGCUCCUAAAUUUGGCUGGCUUUGUUUUUCAUUUGCUUUAGAACUUAUGUGGCAUGACAUAGCUCGAUUGUAUGAGAUUUAACACUUAUUAUGAAACAAAUCUUGAAAUUUGUUUUCACUGGUAGAGCUGAUCUAGAUUUGAUGAGCAGAUUGAGAGACGCUUCUAUUGGAGCAAUUCUUGUAAUUCACCAGAGGUAUCUAGUUGUUGUAUAAGUGCACUGAGUUAGAUCUUAAAAGUUUGAUCAAUCAUUCCAAACCAUUUCAAAUAUGAAUAUUAGAAAGUUCAACUUAGAAGCUUCCCUUUUGUGUUUUCAUGCAUUCAGGUAAAGUCCUAUUUAUGACUCUUAGAAAUGAGGUAGGUUUUAGAGCUAGUCUUCUAACUCGUGAAUAGUUUAAGGACCACAUCAGUUGCAAACCAAGUAUUUGUUGAAUCAGUAAAAUGGCACUAUCAGCAUGAAGAGCCGAGAAGCAGAUCCUGAGGUGUGUCGGACAGUGUUUUAGGUAAUUCAGUAUUUAUUAUGUUAUUAGAGAAGACUUAGCGUAAGAAAGAAAUGCUUUAGAAAUUCCAGCAAGUAUUUAUAAGGCCUGAAAAAACUAAAAUUUGAACAAAAAGGGAAAUAAAUCACACAUUUGUUGAGGCUGCUGCUUUAAGUAUUAGCUAAUUUUCUUGUUUUGGUUUACUUUGAUUUAUUUGAUUGAACCCUGGAAGUAUUAUUUUUACCAGUCCCACAUUUAAAGACCUAGUAAUCUUGAUGGAAUUGGUAAUGGCAGAUAGGGUUUAAUGUUGUUGACUUUUCAAAUUAGAAUUUUUUUUCUAUGAAACUUAGGCUUUUAUAUAACAAAGUAUGUUAUCUCAUUGUUACCGCCGUUUUUCACUACUAGCCUUUUCAGUAUGCCCUUAAAAUGUAUUGGAAAGGUUCCAUGUUAAAUGACAAAUAUCUUUUUCAGUAUGAAUUUUUGAUCUGUAGCCACAAUAAGAUUUUCAUUUUUCAGUGCUCAGGCUCUGUAGCAUGUAUGCUGAAUGCUUUUUUCCUUAGCACCUUUAACAGUAAGGUGUUACUGCAUUUUACAAAACAUCAAUUCAACAUGUCUUGGAUUUAGUUUGUAUUCAUAGAUUUUGUUAAGGAUCAGGCCUGUGAACAUGGGCACAGUGAGGUUAAAUAAUUCACCUGGCCACAACCUGGCUUUGAGGUUCUGCUUUUGGGGGCCAUAAUUUUCAUUCAAUGUUAUUCGAUGCUCUGUUCUGGUGAACAAGUUACUAUACCUGCUGUGUAUAUAAGCUUGAGCUAUACUAAACCAAGGCUUUAUUUUCUUUUGUUUUUUAACUUACUGUACUUUUACUGUUUAUAUAACCUAUAUUUCAAGAGAGAGAAGAUAAUGCUGAAUUUUAAAUUUAGCAUUUGAACAUCUGUCCAAUAGUGAAUUAAUCAGUUUUUUUAAAAUUGAUUUUUAAGUUGUUCCAGAAAAAAAUAUAUAUAUAUGUUUUAUAUAUAUAAUCUUUUUAUAUAUAUAAAAAAUCUUUUUUAUAAAUUUUAUUUUAAAAAUCUUUUAAAAAAGAUUUUUAUAUAUAUAUAAAGAUUAUAUAUUUAUAUAUAGUCUUUUCUGUUCAUAAUGGCAUUAGUCUCUGAGUACAUUUUAUAUUAUCUUUGUUGCCACAUGUCAGGAUACAACACAAUAGUUUUAUAAAUAACAACUGUACUUUGAUUUUAGGUACUAAUUUAAUGCUUUAGUUUUUACUACUUUGAAAGGGGAGGUUCAUCUAAGUAUUACUGAUAACAGGGAUCCAACUUAAAGUAAAAGUUGGAAAGGGCAAGAGUCUUUUAAGCGGAACUUCAAUUCUGUUGUCAUGGUUACUUAUAUAUAAUGAAUAUAAAUAGACAAAUAGGACUUGGAAAAUGUGGUAUAUUCUAAGUCAAGAUGCUAUGAAGUUGUUAUAGUUUAAGGGACAUUCUUAAGAAGGAAUUACUUAAGUACAUUACUCUUCUCAUUUCAAGGACAUGAAAAAGUAAAGGAUGGUCUGGCACUAUUUUAUUUUAUUUUUUUUUUGACUUGUACUGAAUAUAUGUACUUUGAAGAUUUACAUCUAUAACUAGAAAGUAUGCUAAUCCGAGGUCUGGUUAUUAGGCCAGAUUCUUGUUCAGUUAUUUUUUAAACUAAUGUUGCCUCCUUUUUAGUAAGAUUCUACGAAAGUUUUUUAACUAUUAAAGUUAUUUCUUAAGGGGUAGCUCUUAUACUUCCUCUGCUCUCUUUUUCAGUUUCCAUAAAAAGCUGUUUUCUUAGCUAUUACUCCAAAUAAAGUUCUUUGGUUUGCUUAAAAAUGUAGUGUAAUGCAGUUGUUUUCUCUCCGCUAACCUGAGUGUCCACAGUAGAUAUCGAGACAGCUUUAGGAAGGUGACGGUCAUGGGUAAGUGACGGCUGUGCCUGUCAUCUUCAGAUUCUUCAAAUACUGCAAACUAUGAAACAUGUUAAGACCAAUAUAAACCCAAAGAUGUGAGUUGAUUAUACUUUAAUAAUUACAUUCAUAAAAAGUUUACUAUCUUCAAUGCCAAAAAAGUCUUAACCUAUAAAUGAUUAUAUACAAUCUUAGAAAAUGUGCUUAACAGUUAUGGCUUCUUUAUUUCUAUGAGGAAAGAUUAGUAAGAAACUUAAAAUUAACAUCCUUUUAAGAUUUUCUGUUCCAUUUUAAUGUAUUUUAGGCAUUUAGAACUAGCCUGGCAUAAUGAAGAAAGAAAUAAAAGAAUUAAAGAUAA